ACUCUGACUUUCCAGCGCCCAGGCCGGGGCGCCGCCAGGGCGUCUCUGAGGGUCGCGCCCCGAUACCUUCCUCCACCCCACGGCUUCUUCCCCCCAAGGGCGGGGCUGGGGGCCCAGGAGCACCACAGCCCCCAUGGGCCCGGGAAAUGGCAGCUUCGUCAUGGCCCAGCCCGCCACGCUCACCUUUUCCCACCACCUGGAGGAUCCACUCUCCGUCCGUCCUUCCCGACCUCAGGCUGCAGAGGAAACCUGGGGGCGGGGGUCGAGGAAGCCGAGCCCCGAGGCUCCCAGCGCCGCCCCAGGAGGAAUCUUGCGGGCCACUAGAAGCUGUGCGCGCGGCCGGGCUCGGCCCCCACAACGGCCCGAGCGGCCGGGCCUGCCGCGAGCCUCCGCGUCCAGGUGGGGUCUCCGCGCCCCCAUUCCACCCCUCCCCGCCAUCGGCGCUCCCCGCAACUGCGGGGUUUCCACCCGCCCCGGCGCUCGCGCCCACUCACGGUCUCCCUCGCCCCCCCGGGAGAUGCUCCCGGCGUUCUAUCCCGCCCCGCCCUGGCGCGCCCCGCAAACGAUGUGACCCCGGCCCCCUGCGGUCUCCCCUCCUCCGGACGCUGCCCCUGCCCCACCUGUGGCGCUCCCGUCAUCUCUAGAGCCCCCAACCAGAGUCCUCCAGCCCACCCGCGAGGCUCGCGCACCUGCGAUGCGGCCCCACUAGCAGGGACCCGCCCACCUGUGGCGCUACCCCUGCCUCUGCCGCCUCCCGCACCGCUAGCGCGGCCCCCACC